GCGAAAAGCCGGGGCGCCUGCGCUGCCGCCGCCGCGUCUGCUGAAGCCUCCGAGAUGCCGGCGCGUACCGCCCCAGCCCGGGUGCCCACACUGGCCGUCCCGGCCAUCUCGCUGCCCGACGAUGUCCGCAGGCGGCUCAAAGAUUUGGAAAGAGACAGCUUAACAGAAAAGGAAUGUGUGAAGGAGAAAUUGAAUCUCUUGCACGAAUUUCUGCAAACAGAAAUAAAGAAUCAGUUAUGUGACUUGGAAACCAAAUUACGUAAAGAAGAAUUAUCCGAGGAGGGCUACCUGGCUAAAGUCAAAUCCCUUUUAAAUAAAGAUUUGUCCUUGGAGAACGGUGCUCAUGCUUACAACCGGGAAGUGAAUGGACGUCUAGAAAACGGGAACCAAGCAAGAAGUGAAGCCCGUAGAGUGGGAAUGGCAGAUGCCAACAGCCCCCCCAAACCCCUUUCCAAACCUCGCACGCCCAGGAGGAGCAAGUCCGAUGGAGAGGCUAAGCGUUCAAGAGACCCUCCUGCCUCAGCCUCCCAAGUAACUGGGAUUAGAGCUGAACCUUCACCUAGCCCCAGGAUUACAAGGAAAAGCACCAGGCAAACCACCAUCACAUCUCAUUUUGCAAAGGGCCCUGCCAAACGGAAACCUCAGGAAGAGUCUGAAAGAGCCAAAUCGGAUGAGUCCAUCAAGGAAGAAGACAAAGACCAGGAUGAGAAGAGACGUAGAGUUACAUCCAGAGAACGAGUUGCUAGACCGCUUCCUGCAGAAGAACCUGAAAGAGCAAAAUCAGGAACGCGCACUGAAAAGGAAGAAGAAAGAGAUGAAAAAGAAGAAAAGAGACUCCGAAGUCAAACCAAAGAACCAACACCCAAACAGAAACUGAAGGAGGAGCCGGACAGAGAAGCCAGGGCAGGCGUGCAGGCUGACGAGGACGAAGAUGGAGACGAGAAAGAUGAGAAGAAGCACAGAAGUCAACCCAAAGAUCUAGCUGCCAAACGGAGGCCCGAAGAAAAAGAACCUGAAAAAGUAAAUCCACAGAUUUCUGAUGAAAAAGACGAGGAUGAAAAGGAGGAGAAGAGACGCAAAACGACCCCCAAAGAACCAACGGAGAAAAAAAUGGCUCGCGCCAAAACAGUCAUGAACUCCAAGACCCACCCUCCCAAGUGCAUUCAGUGCGGGCAGUACCUGGACGACCCUGACCUCAAAUAUGGGCAGCACCCACCAGACGCGGUGGAUGAGCCACAGAUGCUGACAAAUGAGAAGCUGUCCAUCUUUGAUGCCAACGAGUCUGGCUUUGAGAGUUAUGAGGCGCUUCCCCAGCACAAACUGACCUGCUUCAGUGUGUACUGUAAGCACGGUCACCUGUGUCCCAUCGACACCGGCCUCAUCGAGAAGAAUAUCGAACUCUUCUUUUCUGGUUCAGCAAAACCAAUCUAUGAUGAUGACCCAUCUCUUGAAGGUGGUGUUAAUGGCAAAAAUCUUGGCCCCAUAAAUGAAUGGUGGAUCACUGGCUUUGAUGGAGGUGAAAAGGCCCUCAUCGGCUUCAGCACCUCAUUUGCCGAAUACAUUCUGAUGGAUCCCAGUCCCGAGUAUGCGCCCAUAUUUGGGCUGAUGCAGGAGAAGAUCUACAUCAGCAAGAUUGUGGUGGAGUUCCUGCAGAGCAAUUCCGACUCGACCUAUGAGGACCUGAUCAACAAGAUCGAGACCACGGUUCCUCCUUCUGGCCUCAACUUGAACCGCUUCACAGAGGACUCCCUCCUGCGACACGCGCAGUUUGUGGUGGAGCAGGUGGAGAGUUAUGACGAGGCCGGGGACAGUGAUGAGCAGCCCAUCUUCCUGACACCCUGCAUGCGGGACCUGAUCAAGCUGGCUGGGGUCACGCUGGGACAGAGGCGAGCCCAGGCGAGGCGGCAGACCAUCAGGCAUUCUACCAGGGAGAAGGACAGGGGACCCACGAAAGCCACCACCACCAAGCUGGUCUACCAGAUCUUCGAUACUUUCUUCGCAGAGCAAAUUGAAAAGGAUGACAGAGAAGACAAGGAGAACGCCUUUAAGCGCCGGCGAUGUGGCGUCUGUGAGGUGUGUCAGCAGCCUGAGUGUGGGAAAUGUAAAGCCUGCAAGGACAUGGUUAAAUUUGGUGGCAGUGGACGGAGCAAGCAGGCUUGCCAAGAGCGGAGGUGUCCCAAUAUGGCCAUGAAGGAGGCAGAUGACGAUGAGGAAGUCGAUGAUAACAUCCCAGAGAUGCCGUCACCCAAAAAAAUGCACCAGGGGAAGAAGAAGAAACAGAACAAGAAUCGCAUCUCUUGGGUCGGAGAAGCCGUCAAGACUGAUGGGAAGAAGAGUUACUAUAAGAAGGUGUGCAUUGAUGCGGAAACCCUGGAAGUGGGGGACUGUGUCUCUGUUAUUCCAGAUGAUUCCUCAAAACCGCUGUAUCUAGCAAGGGUCACGGCGCUGUGGGAGGACAGCAGCAACGGGCAGAUGUUUCACGCCCACUGGUUCUGCGCUGGGACAGACACAGUCCUCGGGGCCACGUCGGACCCUCUGGAGCUGUUCUUGGUGGAUGAAUGUGAGGACAUGCAGCUUUCAUAUAUCCACAGCAAAGUGAAAGUCAUCUACAAAGCCCCCUCCGAAAACUGGGCCAUGGAGGGAGGCAUGGAUCCCGAGUCCCUGCUGGAGGGGGACGACGGGAAGACCUACUUCUACCAGCUGUGGUAUGAUCAAGACUACGCGAGAUUCGAGUCCCCUCCAAAAACCCAGCCAACAGAGGACAACAAGUUCAAAUUCUGUGUGAGCUGUGCCCGUCUGGCUGAGAUGAGGCAAAAAGAAAUCCCCAGGGUCCUGGAGCAGCUCGAGGACCUGGAUAGCCGGGUCCUCUACUACUCAGCCACCAAGAACGGCAUCCUGUACCGAGUUGGUGAUGGUGUGUACCUGCCCCCUGAGGCCUUCACGUUCAACAUCAAGCUGUCCAGUCCCGUGAAACGCCCACGGAAGGAGCCCGUGGAUGAGGACCUGUACCCAGAGCACUACCGGAAAUACUCCGACUACAUCAAAGGCAGCAACCUGGAUGCCCCUGAGCCCUACCGAAUUGGCCGGAUCAAAGAGAUCUUCUGUCCCAAGAAGAGCAACGGCAGGCCCAAUGAGACUGACAUCAAAAUCCGGGUCAACAAGUUCUACAGGCCUGAGAACACCCACAAGUCCACUCCAGCGAGCUACCACGCAGACAUCAACCUGCUCUACUGGAGCGACGAGGAGGCCGUGGUGGACUUCAAGGCUGUGCAGGGCCGCUGCACCGUGGAGUAUGGGGAGGACCUGCCCGAGUGCGUCCAGGUGUACUCCAUGGGCGGCCCCAACCGCUUCUACUUCCUCGAGGCCUAUAAUGCAAAGAGCAAAAGCUUUGAAGAUCCUCCCAACCAUGCCCGUAGCCCUGGAAACAAAGGGAAGGGCAAGGGAAAAGGGAAGGGCAAGCCCAAGUCCCAAGCCUGUGAGCCGAGCGAGCCAGAGAUAGAGAUCAAGCUGCCCAAGCUGCGGACCCUGGAUGUGUUUUCUGGCUGCGGGGGGUUGUCGGAGGGAUUCCACCAAGCAGGCAUCUCUGACACGCUGUGGGCCAUCGAGAUGUGGGACCCUGCGGCCCAGGCGUUCCGGCUGAACAACCCCGGCUCCACAGUGUUCACAGAGGACUGCAACAUCCUGCUGAAGCUGGUCAUGGCUGGGGAGACCACCAACUCCCGCGGCCAGCGGCUGCCCCAGAAGGGAGACGUGGAGAUGCUGUGCGGCGGGCCGCCCUGCCAGGGCUUCAGCGGCAUGAACCGCUUCAAUUCGCGCACCUACUCCAAGUUCAAAAACUCUCUGGUGGUUUCCUUCCUCAGCUACUGCGACUACUACCGGCCCCGGUUCUUCCUCCUGGAGAAUGUCAGGAACUUUGUCUCCUUCAAGCGCUCCAUGGUCCUGAAGCUCACCCUCCGCUGCCUGGUCCGCAUGGGCUAUCAGUGCACCUUCGGCGUGCUGCAGGCCGGUCAGUACGGCGUGGCCCAGACUAGGAGGCGGGCCAUCAUCCUGGCCGCGGCCCCUGGAGAGAAGCUCCCUCUGUUCCCGGAGCCACUGCACGUGUUUGCUCCCCGGGCCUGCCAGCUGAGCGUGGUGGUGGAUGACAAGAAGUUUGUGAGCAACAUAACCAGGUUGAGCUCGGGUCCUUUCCGGACCAUCACGGUGCGAGACACGAUGUCCGACCUGCCGGAGGUGCGGAAUGGAGCCUCGGCACUGGAGAUCUCCUACAACGGGGAGCCUCAGUCCUGGUUCCAGAGGCAGCUCCGGGGCGCACAGUACCAGCCCAUCCUCAGGGACCACAUCUGUAAGGACAUGAGUGCAUUGGUGGCUGCCCGCAUGCGGCACAUCCCCUUGGCCCCAGGGUCAGACUGGCGCGAUCUGCCCAACAUCGAGGUGCGGCUCUCAGACGGCACCAUGGCCAGGAAGCUGCGGUAUACCCACCAUGACAGGAAGAACGGCCGCAGCAGCUCUGGGGCCCUCCGUGGGGUCUGCUCCUGCGUGGAAGCCGGCAAAGCCUGCGACCCCGCAGCCAGGCAGUUCAACACCCUCAUCCCCUGGUGCCUGCCCCACACCGGGAACCGGCACAACCACUGGGCUGGCCUCUAUGGAAGGCUCGAGUGGGACGGCUUCUUCAGCACAACCGUCACCAACCCCGAGCCCAUGGGCAAGCAGGGCCGCGUGCUCCACCCAGAGCAGCACCGUGUGGUGAGCGUGCGGGAGUGUGCCCGCUCCCAGGGCUUCCCUGACACCUACCGGCUCUUCGGCAACAUCCUGGACAAGCACCGGCAGGUGGGCAAUGCCGUGCCACCGCCCCUGGCCAAAGCCAUUGGCUUGGAGAUCAAGCUUUGUAUGUUGGCCAAAGCCCGAGAGAGUGCCUCAGCUAAAAUAAAGGAGGAGGAAGCUGCUAAGGACUAGUUCUGCCCUCCCGUCACCCCUGUUUCUGGCACCAGGAAUCCCCAACAUGCACUGAUGUUGUGUUUUUAACAUGUCAAUCUGUCCGUUCACAUGUGUGGUACAUGGUGUUUGUGGCCUUGGCUGACAUGAAGCUGUUGUGUGAGGUUCGCUUAUCAACUAAUGAUUUAGUGAUCAAAUUGUGCAGUACUUUGUGCAUUCUGGAUUUUAAAAGUUUUUUAUUAUGCAUUAUAUCAAAUCUACCACUGUAUGAGUGGAAAUUAAGACUUUAUGUAGUUUUUAUAUGUUGUAAUAUUUCUUCAAAUAAAUCUCUCCUAUAAACCA